AUGGUGUCUGCCCACUGUAGGGAGAAGGAGGGCCAGCCUGACCCUUGGACCUGCUGGGCGUGGGGGAUAGGGGUGGCCACACACCUGCUGUCAGGCAGGGCGGGAGGACGGAGGAGGAGGCCGGAGCUCCACAGACGGCCCCACCUGUUCCUUCUGCACCUCAGAGAAGGGUCGUCACCUCCAUUUAUCCCUGUGUGGACGCCACAGCCCUGGCACCAAGUGGCCGGCUCCGUCAAGGGAAAGCGGGGAAGGACAGAAGGCAAAAGUACUUCUCACCUUGUCUCUGCUCCGGGGCCAGGGCUGAGGGAGGGCACUGGGGACCCCGUCUUUCUGCCUGUGCCCCAGCACGCCACUCCCCGCAGAGUGCUCCACACGACCCAGAUUGCAGGCCUGCUGGGGAGGAAGAAGCUUCAGGCACCAUCCCCUGAGCCCCAGCAGUCCUGUGACAUGGUGCCGUUCACCCCCACCAUUGGACAGGAGAGCCAACUGAGGAACCGGGAGGGGGGCCUGGCCCUGGUGAUUGCCCCCAGCUUGGUGGGGUCUCCUGUUGUCCAGGACCCUGGGAGACCUGGGAUUGCUUCUGUCUGCGGUGGCCUGGCCACCUGGGUGCCGUCCCCUCGGUGGGAACCCUGUCCCCCCCACUCGCCCUCCGCCUCACACCCCCCUGUGACGGGGAACCAGGGCCUCCUGCCGGCAGCCACGUGGGUGACCUUGGAGCAGGUGCCCCCGUCCCAGUCAAAACGCAGGUGGCUGCAGCCCUGGCCAGCAGCCUGCCUGCCACGUCCUGAGAGACCCUUCCUGCUGAAGCUGACGCUCACAUCUGCCAGUGUCACUGGGCUGAGCUUCACUGAGCUUCCCAGGGAUCUUAGAUCUAAUUUGGGAAGCUCUGGGGCUGGAGCCCGCCCUCCCCCUCCACCCAGUGACCGGCCCCUGCUGUCCACCUUUCCUUACACCGGCAGCCCUGUCCUGAGGGGCCGUCUUGCUUCCCUUCGGGGUCUCAUCCCUCCGACUCCCACCCCGCAAAACCUCCAGUGGGCGUGUGGAAGUGCUUCUAGGGGCUCAGUGUUCCCUGGGGGUCACCCCGUGCUGUCUCUGUGA